ACAAUAGUGUUAGGCUGUAAUGUCAUUCUUUAAGAAUCUUUUCCAGUAAACAUUUGUUACUUUUUCAAAGUAAUUGGGAGCUGUUGAGUGUGGAAGCGAAAACCAAGUUAAGAAGUCCUGUUAUUUGGGUCAUGGUCUACGUGAAACAUCAAAGAAACCUGUAACGGAAAACGACUUGUUUGAAAGAGCCAGUUCUCUAUCCAAAUUUACCAAUCAGAAUCUUGCACUGAAAAAAUAAACCAAUCGUGAAUCUCUACGGCCACUUCCGGAAUUUAGCAACCGAUCACUAACAGGGAUCGUCCACAAUCCAAUCAGAGUGAUUCUGUUCCUAUAUAGAGGGGCAAACCAAUCUUCCUAACUCAUUUACUUUGCAGAUGAACUAUGGCGCGUACUAAGCAGACGGCUCGUAAAUCCACAGGCGGUAAAGCACCGCGCAAACAGCUGGCCACUAAGGCAGCUCGCAAGAGCGCUCCGGCCACGGGCGGCGUGAAGAAGCCCCAUCGCUACCGCCCUGGCACCGUGGCUCUGCGCGAGAUCCGUCGCUACCAGAAGUCUACCGAGCUUCUAAUCCGGAAGCUGCCGUUUCAGCGCCUGGUGCGAGAAAUAGCUCAGGACUUCAAGACCGACCUGCGCUUCCAGAGUUCCGCGGUGAUGGCGCUGCAGGAGGCCUGCGAGGCCUACUUGGUGGGGCUUUUCGAGGACACCAACCUGUGCGCUAUUCAUGCCAAACGCGUGACCAUCAUGCCUAAAGACAUCCAGCUUGCCCGCCGCAUUCGUGGGGAGAGGGCGUGAAUUGUUUUGAGUACAAACCUUAAAUCCAAAGGCUCUUCUCAGAGCCAACCACUUUGUCCGUGAAAAGGGCUGUAAUCCUUUGAGACGCAUUAGACCACUAAACUGCACUGAUCCAAAUAGACAUUUGAAAUAGUGGCAUUCAGUUCCCUCGAUGCUUCAUUUAAAUUUCCAAAUUUAAGCGCUCCCUCAGGUUUUCGCCUAGGGCUGGGCCUCCCUACGCUGUUCUCCAUUGGUUUAGCUGGCUUUGUUUUGCUGUUCAGGCCCUCUGCUGCUUUCUUGUACAUUGUUCUCGUUUUCUAAACUCCUGGCCACUUAAUUGUACCCUGCUUAACCCAUCCUCUUGUUUUCUGGCUCAACGCUCUUUCAUGUGGUGGCCUGCAUUUUAGGUCUUAACUGCAUAGGCUUUCAACGCCUUGGUUUUGCCUUUCCUUGAUGUUUAUUUGACCUUGCCCGAGGGGCCAGCGCUUUUGAUCUGCAUCAGGCUGCCUUACUCCACUAGUGUUUUGAGACCCAGCUACUUGCCGGCGACGGUCGGUGCCUUGGGUGCGGUCAACGUUACUCUCUGUGCGCCUGAUACUGGUCUAAGGCUAAGGUUAUUAGCUGGAACACCUAGACCCGUGGCACUAACACACAGCUCUUGCAGACUUGACAGCCUUGCAUAGGUUCUAAACUGCAGGAGUCAAAGCAACGAAGGUGCAGAUGGGUGUGUCUCAAACCUGAGUGCGAAAGGAAAAUGCAGAAAUCAUGAGCCUUUUCAACUUUCCAGUUGAUAUCUUUUGUUUGCUUUUUUCUUUUCUUAUUUAUUUAUUUAUUUAUUUAUUUAUUUAUUUAUUUAUUUAUUUUGAGACGGAGUUUCGCCCUUGUUGCCCAGGCUGGAGUGCAUUGGCGCGAUCUCGGCUCACCGCAACCUCCGCCUCCCGGGUUCAAGCGAUUCUCCUGCCUCAGCCUUCCGAGUAGCUGGGAUUACAGGCAUGAGCCACCUCGCCCGGCCUUCCGGCUGAUAUCUUAAAAGAACUUUUCAACUUUAGUAAAUACCCUGUCUUAAUCAAAUCUCAUUAAAAGUACCCCAUAUUUAUCAACAAAACAUGAAAAUCCUUGGACGGCUUCAAAGUUCUUACAGAAAAUAUUCUGCCUUUCCUUUCCAUACAAAGGCACAGCUUCGAAACUGGUAGGUGAAGGGAAGGAAAAUAAGGAAUUCUGUUACGAAAUCAUACAGGCUGUUAUUUGGAAAUACAGAAGGGUGUAUGUACUAUAUGGGAUACUGCAUGCUAUUUGGAAGAAUUUUGUUUAUUUAAACAUUUCAGCAAAUUCCUCAGUUUUGAUAUGGGGUGCAGUAUUUUUAACUCAUUGAGAAAUUUCUACUAACUUUUUUGAAUGUGCUCUUUUCCCACUAGUUGCACUAAGGAAAGAGGUUAGUCAUGUGGUAAAAUUAAUAGUGACAAAGCUGUAAAUAGCUCUGCAGGCCAAGGUAGCCAUAGUAAGAAGUCCUGGAGAUUUAUGGAAGAAAUUUUUGUUCAUGGAAGCCUGUCAGACAUGAAGAUGUGGGUCUUGUGAAUUGGAGAUUCAGUGCGUGAGGAAAACAGCCUAACUAUCCAUAAUUAAGGUAACUACUGUCAGAUAUUUGUAACAUAGUGAACAUCCUAUUAUGCUAGAUAGAAGCAUUCUCUAUUUGAAUGUUGUUUCCUGUAUCCUGUACUUUCUUUAAGAUUCUAGCUCAACAAGUUUUAACCUGUAUUUCUCUUACAGCUACUGGAAUUCAGUACGUGAGGACUUGGACUUGGUGGGCACAGAAUGCAUCUUUUUAUAUCAUUAAAUCCACCAGAACAUCUAGCAUGGUCAUUUGCCUAAAACAAAGCCUCUGGAAAUUUAGUCAAGUUGAGAUGUAAAAUAAAAGAUUACUGAACAGAA